GUUGUUGACAUUUCCGAGAGAGCGGGAGCGUCUGUACCUCUGCGGCGUCACUGGGAGCCCGACGGAAAACUGCGCUAAAGGCUUGUCUUUCCCCUGCCCGACCGAAGGAGCCGACCUUGCCUGCGCUACAGCUUCCUUAUUUUCGUCGCCUGUUCUCCUGAUCCUGCGUGUUCUAAAAACCCCUUAGGCUUUCCAUGGGUUCCCAGACCAUGGCGGUGGCGCUGCCCAGGGACUUGCGGCAGGACGCCAACCUGGCAAAGAGGAGGCACGCGGAGCUGUGCAGGCAGAAGCGGGUCUUCAACGCCAGAAACAGGAUAAUUGGGGGAGACACUGAAGCCUGGGAUGUUCAAGUUCAUGACCAGAAGAUAAAAGAAGCUACUGAAAAAGCUAGACAUGAAACCUUUGCUGCUGAAAUGAGGCAAAAUGACAAAAUCAUGUGCAUAUUGGAAAACCGGAAAAAGAGGGAUAGGAAAAAUCUCUGUAGGGCUAUCAAUGACUUCCAACAGAGCUUUCAGAAGCCAGAAACUCGCCGUGAAUUUGAUCUGUCCGACCCCCUAGCCCUUAAGAAAGAUCUUCCAGCCCGGCAGUCAGAUAAUGAUGUUCGGAAUACGAUAUCAGGAAUGCAGAAAUUCAUGGGAGAGGAUUUAAACUUCCAUGAGAGGAAGAAAUUCCAAGAGGAACAAAACAGAGAAUGGUCUUUGCAGCAGCAAAGGGAAUGGAAGAACGCCCGUGCUGAACAAAAAUGCGCAGACCUGACCUUCUACCCACAUCCGUGACAGCUCCUUUCUUCUAGCUGCCCAGGCCCCAGCCCAGAGGCCCUCUACACAGAGACAAGGCUGCAGUUUGACGAGACAGCCAAGCACCUCCAGAAGCUGGAAAGCACCACCAGAAAGGCAGUUUGUGCAUCUGUGAAAGACUUCAACAAGAGCCAGGUAUAGGUACUCCGCGACCUCGGGCUCGACGACUGGAGGGGAGGAUGAGCCCACUACGGCUUCCCAAGGCUCUCCGGCUUCCCUGGGAUCCCAGUCUCAGCCUGCUCCCUGGUCACAUGACCGGCCCUGACAGAGACCCUGAUGGGCUGCCUGAUGACAGAGAUGGAUGAGACCCAGUCCUGUGCCUUAGCUCUGAAUCUUGGAGGGAAACCUGCCAAACUAGCCAUGUAACCUGGGGAAGUCAGCUCACCUUUCUACACCUCGGUUUCUUCUUCUGUAACAUGAGGAUGGUGACAUCCACCUAGACUGUUACCGCCUAGCUCUGCUCCACUGCCUGGUGCUGGUUUCCAUUCUUCCCACCUCUCAGACUUCCCCUUUACUGAGAACAGCUACUUGGAUGCUCACCGAUGGCAGGGAUGAUGAAGAAGAUCAUAAUGAGCUCGAACACUGGGGCCUCCUGAGACCUCCCACCUCCUCUCUAAACUCUGGCCCCCCUCCUCCCACACACUCCCCUCCCCUCCAACCUGAUGCUGAAAUUGCUGAAAUAGGUUCUUCUUUUUGUUUC